GAGCAACGCGACUGACCGUGGUCGUGGGCGGACGGCGGCUGCAGCGUGGAGGAGCUGGGGUCGCUGUGGGUCGCGAAGCAGAGCCCGGGACGUGCGCGCUUGGUGCACGAUCCUGAAGGGGAGCUCCGAGGGGCCCGGGUCGCCAGGGCUGCUGCGGCCAUUCCCGGAGCCCGGCGCGGGGCCCGCGAGAUACUGGUUUAGGCCGUCCCAGGGCUCCGGGCGCACCCGGUGGCCGCUGCUGCAGCGGAGGGAGCGCGGCGGCGCGGGGGCUCGGAGACAGCGUUUCUCCCGGAAGUCUUCCUCGGGCAGCAGGUGGGAAGUGGGAGCCGGAGCGGCAGCUGGCAGCGUUCUCUCCGCAGGUCGGCACCAUGCGCCCUGCAGCCCUGCGCGGGGCCCUGCUGGGCUGCCUCUGCCUGGCGUUGCUUUGCCUGGGCGGUGCGGACAAGCGCCUGCGUGACAACCAUGAGUGGAAAAAACUAAUUAUGGUUCAGCACUGGCCUGAGACAGUAUGCGAGAAAAUUCAAAACGACUGUAGAGACCCUCCGGAUUACUGGACAAUACAUGGACUAUGGCCCGAUAAAAGUGAAGGAUGUAAUAGAUCGUGGCCCUUCAAUUUAGAAGAGAUUAAGGAUCUUUUGCCAGAAAUGAGGGCAUACUGGCCUGACGUAAUUCACUCGUUUCCCAAUCGCAGCCGCUUCUGGAAGCAUGAGUGGGAAAAGCAUGGGACCUGCGCCGCCCAGGUGGAUGCGCUCAACUCCCAGAAGAAGUACUUUGGCAGAAGCCUGGAACUCUACAGGGAGCUGGACCUCAACAGUGUGCUUCUAAAAUUGGGGAUAAAACCAUCCAUCAAUUACUACCAAGUUGCAGAUUUUAAAGAUGCCCUUGCCAGAGUAUAUGGAGUGAUACCCAAAAUCCAGUGCCUUCCACCAAGCCAGGAUGAGGAAGUACAGACAAUUGGUCAGAUAGAACUGUGCCUCACUAAGCAAGACCAGCAGCUGCAAAACUGCACCGAGCCGGGGGAGCAGCCGUCCCCCAAGCAGGAAGUCUGGCUGGCAAAUGGGGCCGCCGAGAGCCGGGGUCUGAGAGUCUGUGAAGAUGGCCCAGUCUUCUAUCCCCCACCUAAAAAGACCAAGCAUUGAUGCCCAAGUUUUGGAAAUAUUCUGUUUUAAAAAGCAAGAGAAAUUCACAAACUGCAGCUUUCUAAAAAACAACUCCAAAGUGAAGUCUGUUUAUUUUGCUGUUUCCCCUCCAUGCCUGUGAAUUGGAUGUUGUGGUCCCUGUAGAGUGAGUGCAUGUGGCGUACACGGGGAGAAAGGAGCUCUCCCACGCCUGAGUGGCUGUUUUGUGCUUGGGAUAAAGCUCACAGAUUGUUUUUUUUUUUCUCUAUUAAACUCUUCAGUGCCCUGGUAGAUCAGGCAGGCAUACUUGGAAUUUAGACAGAUGGCACCGAUUCAGGGGACUCUCUUGCUCGAGUUUUCCCCUCGGAGCCUGUUGCCUUCUUGGCGCAGGGACCCUGUCAAGACGAAGAGCUCCACGCAUGGCAGGAGCCCACGCUGAUGCCUGGUGGGCCUGGGGGGUGUCUCUAGCUCAGACUGGGUCUGUUCCAUGUGACCAGAGCCCCAGGACAUCGUUCCUUAGCCAGCUGCUCCGUUGUUGGAGGCCUGGUGUGGUCACAGGUGUGUCCUAGAACGGUGACUUUGCCCCUCCUGCCCUAGGAGAUUUGGGUGUAUUCACAGAGCAGCCAUCUCCUGUCUCCGUCAGAGCAGUCUCUUCCAGGUUACUGGAAGGUCAGUUUCUGUCAGGCCUCACUUCCUUCUUAUCAGAGGGUAGCCAGGUCCCUGCACUGGUAUCUAUUUAGAAAUGUACAUGGAGCCCCCAGCGAAAUGUGCCUACAUUGUGUGUUCCAGAACCGGAGGUACCCUUACCUUCUAGAUAUGUGAUGACAUGGCUCUCACGUCAGGCAGACUGCUGCACCCACGCUCUCGGCCUGCCGUGCAGGGAUUUCACUCGUGGAGUGAGGCAUCUGGGGGCUGUGCAGUGAGGAGCUUUCCAUGUGUUGUUAAGACAACCUGUUAGCAUUGUCUUCUCCCGCGUCUCCUGGCCUCUUCUCUCUUUAAAUCCUUUUCUCUGUUUGUCUUAAUCACAUUAACGUCCUAUUUAUGUUUUAUUCAAUAUACAUUUAAAAUAGAACUUACUAUGUGCCAGGCAUUGUGUUCAACACGUGAAAUAUUUAAUCCUUAGAAUAACCAUAUUGUCAGCAUAAUUUACAAAAAAAAAAAAAACAGCUGUAUCAAUGCCUGUGAAUAUUCGGCUUUACUCGCCCAUUUAAAGAAGAGAUUUUCAAAUUGGCUCAAACCAAAACCUCACUUCAUGGUGUCUACAAGACAGUCUGAAAUGCAGAAUGUUCAGAGAGAGACAAAGGUUUACCAGGCAGAUGGGACGGUGAGAAAGUAGGUGUCGCAGUCCUGAUCCUAGACUCAGUGGCCUCUGCGUCCCCCGCAGGCAUUAAAGGAGACACAGGACGGCCUCUGGCCCUCUGGAAACAAGCUCUGCAGUAAGAGCCUGAGACAGGCAGCACCCAGCCAGGCCUGACAGCUUCUGCAGACAGACAGAGUGAGAUGAUGGGGGAUUUGAUGGAAGCAGUCCCUGUAUUUUGUCUCUUCUGUAAUGGAGGAGCUGAGCCCUCUUCUGCAAGCUGUGGGGAAGGCUAGCGGAGCCCAAGGGUCCAGGGUCCCCACCUUGUCAUUGUCCCUCGGCCCUUCUCUGAGCUCAUUUCUGUCUCCAGUGUUUUUCUGUUGGCUUGGCAGGGCAGGAUUUGUUUCUGUCGGGAACUGAUGAUUUGUGUUUUGAUGCCUGUGAGAGGGACAAGAUCUGAUUUGUUUUGCACCUGGAAGGGCGUGAUUUCCUGCAUUUGCUCUGCGUCCUCAGGGAGUGGGUGUACUUUAGAGUUGGACUCUUAAGCCUCAGAGUCCUUUAAAUGAUGUCAAUUCUUUUUUUUUUUUUUUUUUUUUUUGAGUCAUUUUGCGAACACAGGGAUCAAGGCUUGGGUUUUAUCUUCAUUAUUCCCAGAGGAGCUGGUGAAUUUGAACAGACUUCCUAUUCAAAUUGCAUUUAUUUUAUAGCCUUGGGGGGUCAAGGAAAGCAGCUCUUCAGAGGCUGUCUGCAGUCGGCUGGCCUUUGCGGUUUUUAAAGAAGCCAUUCUUUUUUUUAAGUAGCGUGUAUUUAUUAUAUGAGUGUGAGCAUUUGAGAGCGGAUGGGGACGCCAACAAGGUAGCAUCCUGGUGGGAGGCAUGGGCUGCGGAGUGCUGGUUUCCUGCCAUUGUCACGUCAGCUAAAUGGAAGAAGGCACUGGUGAGGGGCUGGAUGGUUCAAAACAUGAGCACAAGCAAAUGCUUGGCUCUCUUAAUAUUCCUAUUUUGGCCUAGAGCUCAGGAGCAGGUAGAACAUGAGCGUUUGAUAACCUGCCUCAGAUCAUGUAAGUAUAAGGCACUUAUGAGCCGCAGGAGACAGAAGGGGAAGACUCUGCGUUUAAGGUUCAGUGAUGGAGAUCAGAUCCAAGCACAUGUUUUUACAUCAUUAAACAAGUAGGUCGUGCAUUUUCCAGAUUCAACUCAGGAAGAUGCAACUCUGACCACACGGUUCUCGCUGUAACUGGGCGGAGGUGACUGAGAAAUGCCUCCCAUGUGAGCGGGGUCUCAGGCUCGUAUGUGUGGAAGGAGGAGCAGGCCAGGCUCUGGGAUCAGAGCUGGGGGUACAAGUGUCUCCCAGGGGGACAAAGGAGCAGGCGCAUCUCAGGAUGGAGAGCAGCCAGGAGGGGCAGCUGGCCCGGGUCUCAGCCAGAGCAGGCGUCUGCCUGGAGCAUCUCUGCGGCACCAUGGAAAAGAGGACCCGUGGACUAGGCCACAGGGAUGAGUGGAACUUAUGGUGGAAAAAGACACCAUAGGUAAAAGCGAGACAAGAAAACCAGGUUCCCAUGAAACUCCUUCAGACCAGCCCCUUCUCAGCAGGGCUAUUGCUGUACCCAAGAGCAUUUCUCUUGGCCUGGGAGGGGACAAUGCUUUGUCACCUGGAAAGCAAUCCCUCUCUCCAAGCUAGUAGUGGGAGAUCAUUAUGCGCUUGAAUAACUAACAGUAGCAAUUGUAUCAUAUUCAGAACUAGAUAUCUUUUCUUUUCUUUUCUUUUUUUUUUUUUUUGAGACUGAGUCUCACUCUGUCGCCCAGGCUGGAGUGCAGUGGUGCGAUCUCGGCUCACUGCAACCUCUGUCUCCUGGGUUCAAGCAAUUCUUCUGCCUCAGCCUCCCGAGUAGCUGGGACUAGGCACGCCACCAUGCCCGGCUAUUUUUUGUAUUUUUAGUAGAGUUGGGGUUUCACUGUGUUGGCCAGGCUGGUCUGGAACUCCUGACCUCAGGUGAUCUGCCUGCCUCAGCCUCCCAGAGUGCUAGGAUUAUAGGUGUGAGCCACCGCGCCUGGCCCAGGUAUCUUAUCUUUCCACCGAAACUUUUGCCUCCAUCUCGGUGAAUGACAUCACCAUCCGCUUAUUCCAGGUAGAAACCUCAAAGUGAACUGGAAACUUUUUAAAAAAAUUUUGCCUAAAUUGUGAAAGUAUUCUGAAUUAUAUUCAGCUUAUCCUUCUCAUUACUGACUUAGUUCAAGCCUCAGUCUCCCAUCUGGGCCAUGCAUUGACUGCCACGCCACCUGACUGUCAGUGCUGGACGCUGGCACCGUGUUUGUGCCACUCUCCGUAACCAACCAUGGCUCUCUGCUCCCAGAUCACACCUCCCCAGUAUGGCGGCUCAGGGACAUUCCCUCAAUCCCUCCUGCCCUGUUGGCAGUGCCUCCACCCACUCCCCACAGCCCAUGAGGGCUCUGCUUAGCACUUCCUUGUGCCUGGAUUCUCCGCGCAGUUUGGGUGGCCUGGAGUGCUCUUCUGCUCACCUAGUUUAGCAAGUUCCAUGGGAUAUCAACACCCAGUUCCAUGGUUGGCCGUUAAGAGUUCUUUUGCAGUCCUGGGUGGCUCUGCGCCUCCACGCCCAGGGACCAGGGCCUCUUCUCUUCCAGCUCUUGUUGUGUUACAUAGAAGAUGCCAGCUGGAUGGCACAGGGGAGGGCCGUACAGUGUAGAUGCGGACAAUGUGGCAUAGGUGAGGACUGGACAGCAGAGACAGUGGCUGCAUGAUGGAGGUGAGGGCUGGACGGGGGAGGCAAGGGCUGGACCGGGGAGGUGAGGGCUGGACAGGGGAGGUGAGGGCUGGGCAGUAUAGAUGAGGCCUGGGUGGCAGAGGUGAGGGCUGUGCAGUGUAGGUGAGGACGGGCUGGACAGGGGAGGUGAGGGCUAGGCAGUGUAGAUGAGGCCUGGGUGGCAGGAAUGAUGCCUGGAUGGAGGAAGUGAGAGCUGGGUGGCUUGAGUGAGGGCUAGAUGGCAUGGGUGAGGGCUAAGUGGCAUAGAUGAGGCCUGGGCAGCGGAGACAUGGACUGCGCAUCGUAGGUGUCGGCUGGACAGCAAGGGUGAUGCCUGGACAGCAGAGGUGAGGGCUGGGCGGCAGGAGUGAGGGCUGGGCGGCAGGAGUGAGGGCUGGAUGGCGUAGAUGAGGCCUGGGCAGCAGAGGUGAGGGCUGUGCUGUUCCGGUUUUGGGCUAGACGGCAGGGAGAAUGCCUAGAUGACUGGGUAGAGGCCUGGGUGGGAGAAGUGAGGUCUGGACACUGUGGGUGAGGGCUGGAUGGCGUAGAUGAGGCCUGCGCGGUGGAGGUGAGGCCUGUACUUCUCCUGCCACUAAAUCAAGAGCUGUUUAUUGAUUCAUUCCACACUUUUUUCAACCCUUCCUAUGAGCCGCCUCUCUUCUAGGCACUGGGACAUGGCCAUAAGCAGGGAUCUUUUCCUCUUGGGCCCACUCCAAGAGUGGUGGCAUAUGCCACCAUGCCCGGCUAAUUUUGUAUUUUUAGUAGAGAUGGGUUUUCUCCAUGUUGGUCACGCUGGUCUCAAACUCCCGACCUCGGGUGAUCCACCUGCCUCAGCCUCCCAAAGUGCAGGGCAACAGACGGCAAGGGAAAAGAGGAGCAUAGCUGGUGCAUUUGAUGCUGGUAGGUUGGAGGGAGGGAGGAGGUCAGAGUUAUGAAGGCGGCCAGGGAAGGCUUCCUCGGAACCUGAAGAAAGGGAGACAGCAACUGCAGGGAAGGAUCUGUGGGCCCUAAUGGCCACGUCACACUACAAAGGCCCGGACUUUGUCCAACUCGCUUCUGUGCUCCAUGAGUGCACCUGUGUCUGAGGCACAUCAGCUCUAAGCCAGUGUUCUCUAGUGAUGGAGUGAAUAAAUGAAUAAAAUAGAAAAGAGAGGCCGGGCGUGGUGGCUCAUGCCUGUAAUACCAGCACUUUGGGAGGCCAAGGCAGGCGGAUCCCAAGGUCAGGAGUUCGAGACCAGCCUGGACAGUAUGGUGAAACUCCAUCUCUACUAAAAAUACAAAAAUUGGCCGGGCAUGGUGGCGGGCACCUGUAGUCCCAGCUACUCGGGAGGCUGAGGCAGGAGAAUGAAUCACUUGAAGCCAGGAGGCAGAGGUUGCAGUGAGCCGAAAUCACACCAUUGCACUCCAGUCUGGAUGACAGAGCAAGACUCCGUUUCAAAAAAAGAAAAAAAGAGAAUGCAGCACUGGUCCCAGUGGAAGGUGCCUGCUGUUGGCUUCUCACCACGCCCAGAUGAGGAAACAUGCAGAUCGCCUGUUUUCACUUUUUGUUUCUGCGAACUUUGGAUCAGGAAUAAAAAUAAUUUAAUGCAGGUCCUAAGGCAGCUGAGAAUUGUAAUGUAAAAUAUUUUCAGAAUUCAACUAUAUUGGCUAGAUCUAUCACUGCAGAAGGCUGGAAAAGACUCAGAAGUUAAAAUACUACUUUUCCUCACAAGCUCUAGCUCCUGAAAUGAAAUUACCAGGAUACAAUCACAGAUAUGAAGUCAGUAUUUGGGCGUCUAUAGAAAAGAAGUCCAUUGCAUUGCUUAUGGGAUGAGCUACGUUUCCCAUAGAAGGGGCAGUAGUGAGGGUUUUCUUAUCUGAAGCAAAAUCUCUGACAGAUGAUGAGAAAUGCAGUUUUAUGUCAUUUUUUUUCUGAUAAGAAUUCUAUUUUUUUUUUCUGAGUGACUGUAAUGGGCCUUCCAUUUAUUUUAGACAAAAAAGACAGAAUUAGCAUUUUAGGCUCAGAUGAUAGUUAUUAGAAAGUUUGAGAUGGGCCAGGCGCAGUGGCUUAUACCUGUAAUCCUAGCACCUUGGGAGGCCGAGGUGGGCGGAUCACUUGAGGUCAAGCGUUCAAGACCACCCUGGCCAACAGGACGAAACCCUAUCUCUACUAAAAAUACAUUAGCUGGGUGUGGUGGCGGGUGUCUGCAAUCCCAGCUACUCAGGAGGCUGAGGUGAGAGGAUGGCUUGAACCCAGGAGGUGGAGGCUGCAGUGAGCCGAGACUGUACUCAAGCUUGGGCAACAGAGUAAGACUCUGUCUCAAAAAAAAAAAAAAAAAAAAAGGCCGGGCCUGGUGGCUCACGCCUGUAAUCCCAGCCCUCUGGGAGGCUGGAGGUUGCAGUGAGUGGAGAUUGCGCCACUGCGCUCCACCCUCCAGCCUGGGCAACAGAGUGAGACUCCAUCUCCAAAAGAAAGUUUGAGAUGGAUAAAGUUAAGAUCCAUUAAAUGCUGUAUGGACUUUAUGCUGACGUGCUUUUCACAUUUCAGACCUGUGCAUUCUUAUGCAUUUACAUUCCCUUUAUUUGAGGGAGCAAGAAUUACACAAUCACCUUUUCCUACCCGCUUUUAACACUGAGAAAAGUCUGCAGAGUGACAGUGGCCCAUUUUUACCAGCAAAGACAUUGAACCUGGCGUGUACAGCUUUGGUGGUUGGUACCUGUCACCAUCUGCUCUUCUGUCUUGAUGACCAUAUGUCUUGGACUGCACCCUGAGAUGUGGGCUGCUCGUGCUGCCCCAGUACUGAACACAGCUACUUGAGCAUAGUAGGUGUUUUGAAAAUAUUUAACCUGAAUUGAGAAAAGAUAGUCAGCAGUGGCCCAAAGAUAACAACAUACAUCAAAAGUCAUGUACAAGAUUCAGCCAGUCACCAAGAUGCUCCCAAUAUUCAGGGGCUUGGUACCUCACUAAUCAAAACUGAAAUGUCACCCGAUUGGUUUUUCUCUGAAUGUUUUAGAGCAGAAUAGACUCAGCCAUGGGAAGAGACAUUUGAGUGGACUCUAUUCAGGUUGAUUGGAGUCUCCUCCAGGUUAAUCAUUCCACUUAAGUCAAUGAGUGAAAUUUUAUACACCUGAGACUCUAGCCUAUGGCAAUUCCUGGAAAUCAAGUGGUUUUUUUGAUGGGGAGCCGGGGGAUGGUCAGUGGGAUGCAACUUGCUGAUGAUGAGAGAUGAGGUGUAAGAUAUUAUCAGGCAAACACCAACGAAACAGGCUUUACUAUAACUCAGAUCACCGCGCUUUUUGAGUGUGUCAGUGAGUAAUCCAUAAUCACAUUUAUAGAUACUUCUUUCACAUUUAUAAUAAUGUCCCCAACAUAAACAUGUAAACAUGAUCAACAUAUAUGCUUAGCAGUUAGGAUCCUAUAGUUAUCAAUAAAAAGUGGAAGCUGUCUUUAAAAACAGA